GGGUUCGCGGUGCUCGCUGAGGCGGCGGUGGCUACGGCUGGAGGAGCCGGGCCGAGGCCGCGGCGGAGGCCGCGGCUGGUACUGGGAGGGUGGCAGGGAGGGACGGGGAAGGAAGAUGGCGACGUCGGGGGCGAACGGGCCUGGUUCGGCCACGGCCUCGGCUUCCAAUCCGCGCAAAUUUAGUGAGAAGAUUGCGCUGCAGAAGCAGCGUCAGGCCGAGGAGACGGCGGCCUUCGAGGAGGUGAUGAUGGACAUCGGCUCCACCCGGUUACAGGCCCAAAAACUGCGACUGGCAUACACAAGGAGCUCUCAUUAUGGUGGGUCUCUGCCCAAUGUUAACCAGAUUGGCUCUGGCCUGGCCGAGUUCCAGAGCCCCCUCCACUCACCUUUGGAUUCAUCUCGGAGCACUCGGCACCAUGGGCUGGUGGAACGGGUGCAGCGAGAUCCUCGAAGAAUGGUGUCCCCACUUCGCCGAUACACCCGCCACAUUGACAGCUCUCCCUAUAGUCCUGCCUACUUAUCUCCUCCCCCAGAGUCUAGCUGGCGAAGGACGAUGGCCUGGGGCAAUUUCCCUGCAGAGAAGGGGCAGUUGUUUCGACUACCAUCUGCACUUAACAGGACAAGCUCUGACUCUGCCCUUCAUACAAGUGUGAUGAACCCCAGUCCCCAGGAUACCUACCCAGGCCCCACACCUCCCAGCAUCCUGCCCAGCCGACGUGGGGGUAUUCUGGAUGGUGAAAUGGACCCCAAAGUCUUUCUCUUUCAAGUACCUGCUAUUGAGGAGAACUUGCUAGAUGACAAGCAUUUGCUGAAGCCAUGGGAUGCUAAGAAGCUAUCCUCAUCCUCUUCCCGACCUCGGUCCUGUGAAGUCCCUGGAAUUAACAUCUUUCCAUCUCCUGACCAGCCUGCCAAUGUGCCUGUCCUCCCACCUGCCAUGAACACGGGGGGCUCCCUACCUGACCUCACCAACCUGCACUUUCCCCCACCACUGCCCACCCCCCUGGACCCUGAAGAGACAGCCUACCCUAGCCUGAGUGGGGGCAACAGUACCUCCAAUUUGACCCACACCAUGACUCACCUGGGCAUCAGCAGGGGCAUGGGCCUGGGCCCAGGCUAUGAUGCACCAGGACUUCAUUCACCUCUCAGCCACCCAUCCCUGCAGUCCUCCCUAAGCAAUCCCAACCUCCAGGCUUCCCUGAGCAGUCCUCAGCCCCAGCUUCAGGGCUCCCACAGCCACCCCUCUCUGCCUGCCUCCUCCUUGGCCCGCCAUGUACUGCCCACCACCUCCCUGGGCCACCCCUCACUCAGUGCUCCGGCUCUCUCCUCCUCCUCUUCCUCCUCCUCCACUUCAUCUCCUGUUUUGGGCGCCCCCUCUUACCCUGCUUCUACCCCUGGGGCCUCCCCCCACCACCGCCGUGUGCCCCUCAGCCCCCUGAGUUUGCUCGCGGGCCCAGCCGACGCCAGAAGGUCCCAACAGCAGCUGCCCAAACAGUUUUCGCCAACAAUGUCACCCACCUUGUCUUCCAUCACUCAGGGCGUCCCCCUGGAUACCAGUAAACUGUCCACUGACCAGCGGUUACCCCCAUACCCAUACAGCUCCCCAAGUCUGGUUCUGCCUACCCAGCCCCACACCCCAAAGUCUCUACAGCAGCCAGGGCUGCCCUCUCAGUCUUGUUCAGUGCAGUCCUCAGGUGGGCAGCCCCCAGGCAGGCAGUCUCAUUAUGGGACACCGUACCCACCUGGGCCCAGUGGGCAUGGGCAACAGUCUUACCACCGGCCAAUGAGUGACUUCAACCUGGGGAAUCUGGAGCAGUUCAGCAUGGAGAGCCCAUCAGCCAGCCUGGUGCUGGAUCCCCCUGGCUUUUCUGAAGGGCCUGGAUUUUUAGGGGGUGAGGGGCCAAUGGGUGGCCCCCAGGAUCCCCACACCUUCAACCACCAGAACUUGACCCACUGUUCCCGCCAUGGCUCAGGGCCUAACAUCAUCCUCACAGGGGACUCCUCUCCAGGUUUCUCUAAGGAGAUUGCAGCAGCCCUGGCCGGAGUGCCUGGCUUUGAGGUGUCAGCAGCUGGAUUGGAGCUAGGGCUUGGGCUAGAAGAUGAGCUGCGCAUGGAGCCACUGGGCCUGGAAGGGCUAAACAUGCUGAGUGACCCCUGUGCCCUGCUGCCUGAUCCUGCUGUGGAGGAGUCAUUCCGCAGUGACCGGCUCCAAUGAGGGCACCUCAUCACCAUCCCUCUUCUUGGCCCCAUCCCCCACCACCAUUCCUUUCCUCCCUUCCCCCUGGCAGGUAGAGACUCUACUCUCUGUCCCCAGAUCCUCUUUCUAGCAUGAAUGAAGGAUGCCAAGAAUGAGAAAAAGCAAGGGGUUUGUCCAGGUGGCCCCUGAAUUCUGCGCAAGGGAUGGGCCUGGGGGAACUCAAGGGAGGGCCUAAAGCACUUGUAACUUUGAACCGUCUGUCUGGAGGUCAGAGCCUGUUGGAAAGCAGGGGUAGAGGGGAGCCCUGGAAGCAGGGCUUUUCCGGAUGCCUAGGGGUGGGCAGUGCCAGCCCCUCCUCACCACUCUUCCCCUUGCAGUGGAGGAGAGAGCCAGAGUGGAUACUAUUUUUUAUUAAAUAUAUUAUUAUAUGUUAAUAAAAAAAUCAUAUCAAA